AUCCCCUCGACCGCUCGCGUCGCAUUUGGCCGCCUCCCUACCGGCCCUCUGCUGCCAGCUCCAAGCCCAGCCCUCAGCCAUGGCAUGCCCCCUGGAUCAGGCCAUUGGCCUCCUCGUGGCCAUCUUCCACAAGUACUCCGGCAGGGAGGGUGACAAGCACACCCUGAGCAAGAAGGAGCUGAAGGAGCUGAUCCAGAAGGAGCUCACCAUUGGCUCGAAGCUGCAGGAUGCUGAAAUUGCAAGGCUGAUGGAAGACUUGGACCGGAACAAGGACCAGGAGGUGAACUUCCAGGAGUAUGUCACCUUCCUGGGGGCCUUGGCUUUGAUCUACAAUGAAGCCCUCAAGGGCUGAAAAUAAAUAGGGAAGAUGGAGACACCCUCUGGGGGUCCUCUCUGAGUCAAAUCCAGUGGUGGGUAAUUGUACAAUAAAUUUUUUUUGGUCAAAUUUA